ACCCCCAAACCCUCUCACCCGCGGCAGUCCGGUGCGAGGCCCCCUCCGGAAGGUGAGGGGAAUGGAUUGGACUCCGGUGGGGAAAGCGGGUGUCUAGAAGUGGUGCUAAUGGGAAGAGAAUUCUGGUUUCAAAAGAGGAUGCUCUGCCACAAAGAGCGGCUCGCGCGCUGGCCUGGGCUCUAGCCGAGGAGAGAUCCCGGGAGAACUCCAGAGCUCCGGGGGAGCGCUCCUCGGAAGACCGGGGCCAACAUGCCUGUGCGCAGGGGGCAUGUGGCACCACAAAAUACAUUUCUGGGGACCAUCAUUCGGAAAUUUGAAGGGCAAAAUAAAAAAUUUAUCAUUGCAAAUGCCAGAGUGCAGAACUGUGCCAUCAUUUAUUGCAACGAUGGGUUCUGUGAGAUGACUGGUUUCUCCAGGCCAGAUGUCAUGCAAAAGCCAUGCACCUGCGACUUUCUCCAUGGACCCGAGACCAAGAGGCAUGAUAUUGCCCAAAUUGCCCAGGCAUUGCUGGGGUCAGAAGAGAGGAAAGUGGAGGUCACCUACUAUCACAAAAAUGGGUCCACUUUUAUUUGUAACACUCACAUAAUUCCAGUGAAAAACCAAGAGGGCGUGGCUAUGAUGUUCAUCAUUAAUUUUGAAUAUGUGACGGAUAAUGAAAACGCUGCCACCCCAGAGAGGGUAAACCCAAUAUUACCAAUCAAAACUGUAAACCGGAAAUUUUUUGGGUUCAAAUUCCCUGGUCUGAGAGUUCUCACUUACAGAAAGCAGUCCUUACCACAAGAAGACCCCGAUGUGGUGGUCAUCGAUUCAUCUAAACACAGUGAUGAUUCAGUAGCCAUGAAGCAUUUUAAGUCUCCUACAAAAGAAAGCUGCAGCCCCUCUGAAGCAGAUGACACAAAAGCUUUGAUACAGCCCAGCAAAUGUUCUCCCUUGGUGAAUAUAUCCGGACCUCUUGACCAUUCCUCUCCCAAAAGGCAAUGGGACCGACUCUACCCUGACAUGCUGCAGUCAAGUUCCCAGCUGUCCCAUUCCAGAUCAAGGGAAAGCUUAUGUAGUAUACGGAGAGCAUCUUCGGUCCAUGAUAUAGAAGGAUUCGGCGUCCACCCCAAGAACAUAUUUAGAGACCGACAUGCCAGCGAAGACAAUGGUCGCAAUGUCAAAGUUUCACGUUCCUGGAUGGCAGGGGGGCCUUUUAAUCAUAUCAAGUCAAGCCUCCUGGGAUCCACAUCAGAUUCAAACCUCAACAAAUACAGCACCAUUAACAAGAUUCCACAGCUCACUCUGAAUUUUUCAGAGGUCAAAACUGAGAAAAAGAAUUCAUCACCUCCUUCUUCAGAUAAAACCAUUAUUGCACCCAAGGUUAAAGAUCGAACACACAAUGUGACUGAGAAAGUGACCCAGGUUCUCUCUUUAGGAGCAGAUGUCCUACCUGAAUACAAACUGCAGACACCACGCAUCAACAAGUUUACGAUAUUGCACUACAGCCCUUUCAAGGCAGUCUGGGACUGGCUUAUCCUGCUGUUGGUCAUAUACACUGCUAUAUUUACUCCCUACUCUGCAGCCUUCCUCCUCAAUGACAGAGAAGAACAGAAAAGACGAGAAUGUGGCUAUUCUUGUAGCCCUUUGAAUGUGGUAGACUUGAUUGUGGAUAUUAUGUUUAUCAUAGAUAUUUUAAUAAACUUCAGAACAACAUAUGUAAAUCAGAAUGAAGAAGUGGUAAGUGAUCCCGCCAAAAUAGCAAUACACUACUUCAAAGGCUGGUUCCUGAUUGACAUGGUUGCAGCAAUUCCUUUUGACUUGCUGAUUUUUGGAUCAGGUUCUGAUGAGACAACAACAUUAAUUGGUCUUUUGAAGACUGCCCGACUCCUCCGUCUUGUGCGCGUGGCCAGGAAACUGGAUCGAUAUUCAGAAUAUGGCGCUGCUGUUCUAAUGCUCUUAAUGUGCAUCUUUGCCCUGAUUGCUCACUGGCUGGCUUGCAUUUGGUAUGCGAUUGGGAAUGUAGAAAGGCCUUACCUGACUGACAAAAUCGGAUGGUUGGAUUCCUUAGGACAGCAAAUUGGGAAACGUUACAAUGACAGUGACUCAAGUUCUGGACCAUCCAUUAAAGACAAAUACGUCACAGCACUUUAUUUUACCUUCAGCAGUUUAACCAGUGUAGGAUUCGGGAAUGUGUCUCCUAACACGAAUUCGGAGAAAAUCUUUUCAAUUUGUGUCAUGUUGAUUGGCUCACUAAUGUAUGCAAGCAUUUUUGGGAAUGUAUCUGCAAUUAUCCAAAGACUAUACUCGGGAACUGCCAGGUACCACAUGCAGAUGCUGCGAGUAAAAGAGUUCAUUCGCUUUCACCAAAUCCCCAACCCUCUGAGGCAACGUCUUGAAGAAUAUUUCCAGCACGCAUGGACUUACACCAAUGGCAUUGACAUGAACAUGGUCCUAAAGGGUUUCCCAGAAUGCUUACAAGCAGACAUUUGUCUACAUCUCAACCAGACAUUGCUGCAAAACUGCAAAGCCUUUCGGGGGGCAAGUAAAGGUUGCCUUAGAGCUUUGGCAAUGAAGUUCAAAACCACCCAUGCACCUCCAGGAGACACCCUCGUUCACUGUGGGGAUGUCCUCACUGCACUUUAUUUCUUAUCCAGAGGCUCCAUUGAAAUUCUCAAAGAUGACAUUGUGGUGGCUAUUCUGGGAAAAAAUGAUAUAUUUGGAGAAAUGGUUCAUCUUUAUGCCAAACCUGGAAAGUCUAAUGCAGAUGUAAGAGCCCUCACAUACUGUGACUUGCAUAAGAUUCAGCGAGAAGACUUGUUAGAGGUUUUGGAUAUGUAUCCUGAGUUUUCUGAUCACUUUCUAACAAACCUAGAGUUGACUUUCAACCUAAGGCAUGAGAGCGCAAAGGCUGAUCUCCUACGAUCACAAUCCAUGAAUGAUUCAGAAGGAGACAACUGUAAACUAAGAAGAAGGAAAUUGUCAUUUGAAAGUGAAGGAGAGAAAGAAAACAGUACAAAUGAUCCUGAAGACUCUGCAGAUACCAUAAGACAUUAUCAGAGUUCCAAGAGACACUUUGAAGAGAAAAAAAGCAGAUCCUCAUCUUUCAUCUCCUCCAUUGAUGAUGAACAAAAGCCGCUCUUCUCAGGAAUAGUAGACUCUUCUCCAGGAAUAGGGAAAGCAUCUGGGCUCGAUUUUGAAGAAACAGUGCCCACCUCAGGAAGAAUGCACAUAGAUAAAAGAAGUCACUCUUGCAAAGAUAUCACUGACAUGCGAAGCUGGGAACGAGAAAAUGCACAUCCCCAGCCUGAAGACUCCAGUCCAUCUGCACUUCAGCGAGCUGCCUGGGGUAUCUCUGAAACCGAAAGCGACCUCACCUACGGGGAAGUGGAACAAAGAUUAGAUCUGCUCCAGGAGCAACUUAACAGGCUUGAAUCCCAAAUGACCACUGACAUCCAGACCAUCUUACAGUUGCUGCAGAAACAAACCACUGUGGUCCCCCCAGCCUACAGUAUGGUAACAGCAGGAUCAGAAUAUCAGAGACCCAUCAUCCAGCUGAUGAGAACCAGUCAACCGGAAGCAUCCAUCAAAACUGACCGAAGUUUCAGCCCUUCCUCACAAUGUCCUGAAUUUCUAGACCUUGAAAAAUCUAAACUUAAAUCCAAAGAAUCCCUUUCAAGUGGGGUGCAUCUGAACACAGCUUCAGAAGACAACUUGACUUCACUUUUAAAACAAGACAGUGAUCUCUCUUUAGAGCUUCACCUGCGGCAAAGAAAAACUUACGUUCAUCCAAUUAGGCAUCCUUCUUUGCCAGAUUCAUCCCUAAGCACUGUAGGAAUCGUGGGUCUUCAUAGGCAUGUUUCUGAUCCUGGUCUUCCAGGGAAAUAAUCAUUUUGUACUAUUUACUCCACAUACAAUGUAAGUGCUUUUAAUGGCUGUUUUCCUUUUUCUAUUUAAAUCCUCUCUACUUGACUCAGGGGCUCACAAGGUACCAUUAUAUGCAAAAGUACUGUAUAUUUUCCUAAAUUGAAGCUUGUAAGGUAAAACUGAGCAGUUAGGAUGUAAAUAUACAUAAGAACUUUUGGUUCCAAAUGUUAAAACUGCCAGCAUCUCACGGCACCUUAUUUUUUAUUUUUAUUUUUUAAAUCACAUGCAUGUUAGGAAACUCCAAUUUCUCUUGCAUGGAGACUCCUAUUUACUGCUUUUACUAAACCAGUACUUCGUUAUGAAAAUGCCUUCCACGCAAAUAAGAAACCAAGGGAUAAAACUGUUCAUGGAUGCAACUCAAAUUCAGAUGAUCCUCAACUCAU